GUAUUAGCCGGAGCCGGCUCGCUAAUGGUGGACGCGUGAGGCGGAGGCGCGGGCGGAGGAGGGAGGCCGGAGCGGGCAGCGCGGCGGCGCCAUGUCCGUGAACAUGGACGAGCUCAAGCACCAGGUCAUGAUCAACCAGUUCGUGCUGACGGCGGGCUGCGCGGCCGACCAGGCGAAGCAACUGCUGCAGGCGGCCCACUGGCAGUUCGAGGUGCGCGGCGCCGGAGCCGGGCGAGGGCCGGGGCCACGGGCGGAGUGUGUCCCGCGUGGCCGCCGGGCGGGGGCGGACGGCGUGGACGCGUGCCGGCUGUGCGCCCCCUCCGGGCCGCAGACCCGACCCGCUUUCCCGACGGCGGUGCCCGGCGUCCGGAUCCCAAGGGCUCGCGGCGGGCGGAGACAGCCCUCAGCGCCUUUUUCCAGGAGACCAACAUCCCCUACAGCCACCAUCACCACCAGAUGAUGUGCACCCCCGCCAAUACCCCUGCUACACCCCCCAACUUCCCUGACGCUCUCACCAUGUUCUCCCGUCUCAAGGCCUCCGAGAGCUUCCACAGCGGUGGCAGCGGCAGCCCGAUGGCCGCGACAGCCACGUCACCCCCGCCACACUUCCCCCAUGCCGCCACCAGCAGCUCUGCGGCCUCCAGCUGGCCCACGGCGGCCUCGCCCCCGGGGGGCCCACAGCACCACCAGCCACAGCCGCCCCUGUGGACUCCAACACCCCCUUCUCCGGCUUCAGACUGGCCACCCCUGGCCCCCCAACAGGCCACCUCAGAACCCAGGGCCCACCCUGCCAUGGAGGCAGAGAGAUAAGGGAGGCCCCUCCCCCCUCCCGGAGGCCAGGACCCCGUGGGGCGGGGGAGAGGACGUCUCUGCGGGCCCCCUUCACCCCUUUUCUGUCUGCACCCCUUGUUCCCCGGAGCCCUGGAGGGGAGAGCGCGGACUCUAGCCAGGCAGGGACACGUCUGGUGCCAGAACACGCAGCUGCCCACACGCAAGGUCAUGGCCCCAGCGGCCCCGGCACAUGGAGUGGUUCAGCGCGGCCUGGGUGCCUGGCGGACAGAACUUCAGAGACCACGCAGCCUUCCUUCGAAGACGCACCUGCCCAGCCCAGCCCAGGGGUGCCGUGGAGGACCACCCUGGCAGAGACAUUGCUGAUCCCUGGCUUGGAGCUCCUUGGGGGCCGGCAGGCCUCGACCCCCACCCUAGGGAAUGCAGAGCCUCUCCGCAUGUGUGCGCGUGGCCGUGUCUGUGUAUUUCUACGUGUGUCGCUCUUCAGAAGCAACCUAGUUCCUGGGGCAGCUGGACUUUGCAUGUUAGUGUGAGCCCCCAGCCCCCUGCCCGCCGCCCCCUCCCCAGGGCCCUGCCUCCUCCCCACCCCCUCGUCAGCCAGCGUUGCUGUUCCUUGCAGAGAAAAGGAUUGUGGGAAACUCCAGGACUCUUCCCACCGCCUCCCAGCGCCUGCCUGCUGGGGCUGCCUGCAUGCCUCCCCUGCACCUGGGGGUACCCGCAUCCACUUCCUUUCCCCCUUUUAACAAAAGAGAAGAACGAAUUCCAAACCA